CUCUCUGGGAUGUGUAGCUUUGGAAAUCUGUCUUUGUUGCUCUGGGAGAGGGGACUCCUGGAAUGUGUCUGUGAAUAAAGACUAGCCGAAGGUGCGAAGUGACUAGACGGGAGCAAAGGAGGAAAACUAGGGAAUGGGAGGUGAGAGUGGCUGACACCGACCCAACGUCCGGGUUGCCGGAAGGCUGCAGCGCCCGGAGCGGUGUCGGGCAAACCGCUACCCUGGUAUUGCUGGAGCCUCUCCUGGGGACUUUUGAACAGAUACUGUGGCCUCAUGAAUAGGAAUGUCUGCCCAUAUGUCAGGAUUGGAAAUAAUGGAUGAAGAUCAAUUAAUCAAAGACGUCUUGGAUAAAUUCCUUAAUUGUCAUGAGCAAACAUAUGAUGAAGAAUUUCUGAACACUUUUACUCAUCUUUCACAAGAGGAUCAUGUGUCCAAAAGGGGAGUGUUUGGAACUGAUUCUUCAGAAAACAUUUUUACCUCAGCAAAAGUUACUCAUAAAAAUGAAGCAGAUGACUACCAUCUUAGAAAUAAAACCAUCUUUCUUCGUACUUCAUCACAAUGUUUGGAAGAACAGGUAGAUAAUUUCCUAGAUUUAGAAGAUUUGGACAUGGAUGAAGAGAUUAAACCCCAAAUGAGUGAGGAUUUGCUGCUGCUUCCAGGAGAAGUGGAGCAGGAUGUAAGCACCAGCAUUCCUUCCUGUAUCCCUUUUGUGGCCCAGCCUCCUACCUGUGAAGUGAAGCCAAAGCCCAGUGUUAAAAGAAUGGACAAACAGACGGAAGAGAUACUUGGAGAUGAAGUUCAACUUUUUUCACUUGAUGAAGAAUUUGAUUAUGACAAUGUGAUGCUAACCUCCAAGUUUAGUCCUGCAGAGAUAGAGAACAUCAAAGAGCUAUGCAAGCAGCAGAAGAGAAAGGACACCAGCCCAGACUUAGAGAAAUCCUGUGACUGAUUCACAGAGGCAUUUUGUGUGUGUGUGCUUAUUUUAAUUUUGUUCUUAUUCUAGCAACAUUAGAAUAAAAGAUAAACCUACUAUAA